AGAAGGUUUCCUGGCCUGUUGCAGCCAUGGUGCAUUGCAGUUGCGUGUUGUUCAGAAAGUAUGGAAAUUUCAUCGAUAAGCUAAGACUCUUCACCAGGGGAGGAUCCGGUGGAAUGGGUUAUCCUCGUUUAGGUGGAGAAGGUGGAAAAGGUGGUGAUGUCUGGGUUGUAGCCCAGAACAGAAUGACUUUAAAACAACUUAAAGACAGGUAUCCUCGGAAACGGUUUGUGGCUGGAGUAGGAGCAAACAGCAAAAUUAGUGCACUGAAAGGCUCCAAAGGAAAAGACUGUGAAAUCCCUGUGCCUGUGGGUAUUUCAGUAACUGAUGAAAAUGGUAAAAUUAUAGGAGAACUCAAUAAAGAAAAUGACAGAAUUUUGGUAGCUCAAGGAGGUCUUGGUGGUAAAUUACUUACAAAUUUCUUACCAUUGAAAGGCCAGAAACGAAUAAUUCACCUUGAUCUAAAACUUAUAGCUGAUGUAGGCCUAGUAGGAUUCCCAAAUGCUGGAAAAUCCUCUUUGCUAAGUUGUGUUUCUCAUGCAAAACCUGCAAUUGCAGAUUACGCAUUUACAACAUUAAAGCCUGAACUUGGAAAGAUAAUGUACAGUGAUUUCAAACAGAUAUCAGUAGCUGAUCUUCCGGGUUUAAUAGAAGGAGCACAUAUGAACAAAGGAAUGGGCCACAAAUUCCUCAAGCAUAUAGAAAGAACUAGACAACUACUUUUUGUUGUUGAUAUUUCUGGAUUUCAGCUUUCUUCUCACACUCAAUACAGGACAGCUUUUGAAACCAUAAUACUGCUUACAAAAGAGUUGGAAUUGUACAAAGAGGAACUUCAGACAAAACCUGCACUCUUGGCAGUUAAUAAAAUGGACUUGCCAGAUGCCCAAGAUAAGUUCCAUGAAUUGAUGAGCCAGCUCCAGAAUCCUAAAGAUUUUCUGCAUUUAUUUGAAAAAAACAUGAUUCCAGAGAGGACUGUAGAGUUCCAACAUAUCAUCCCCAUAUCUGCAGUUACUGGAGAAGGAAUCGAAGAAUUAAAGAAUUGUAUAAGAAAGUCACUGGAUGAACAGGCCAACCAGGAAAAUGAUGCACUUCAUAAGAAACAGUUGCUUAAUUUGUGGAUUUCUGAUACAAUGUCUUCUACUGAGCCACCAUCAAAGCAUGCUGUUACUACUUCCAAAAUGGAUAUAAUUUAAAUAUAUUAAAAAUGGUAUUGAUGGAACAGUAUUUAAUGCUUAAAAACAAGGAAAUCCUUUCAUCUGUGACAACCUGGAGGACAUGUUAAGUAAAAUAAGCCAGGCUUAGAAAGACAAAUGCUGCAUAAUCUCACUGUGGAAUCUUAAGUUGAACUCAUAGAAGGAGAGAAUAGAAUGGUGGUUAUCAAGGGCUGGUGGGGCAGUGGAGGAUUGAGGAGAUAUUGGUCAAAAUUUACAAAAUUUCAGUUAGACAAGGCAACUGAGUUCAAGAGAUCUGUUGUACAGCUUGGUGACUGUAAUUAACAACAAUGUAUUUUGAAAGUCACUGAGUAAAUUUUAAGUGGUUUUUCCAAAAAAGCACAUAAGGUAAUGCACGUUAAUUAGCUAUAUUGAGCCAUUCCACAAUGUAUAGAUAUUUCAAAACAUGUUACACAUGAUAAAUCCAGUUUUUCUACGUCAUUUUUUAAAAUUAUAUUUAAUUUUUUUAUUUUGAAAGUUUUUUCACAGAUCUUUUUUUUAGUAUUAUUACCUUCUGAUAUAUGUGUCAUUAUUGAAGAACCAUACCUUUUAAAGUUAUUAUUUUGUAAUUAAGUAUGUCAACAGUAAAAAAUAACCAGUGGCCAGGCAUGGUGGCUCAUGCCUGUAAUCCCAGCACUUUUCGGAGGCCGAGGAGGGCAGAUCACUUGAGGUCAGGAGUUCAAGACCAGCCUGGCCAACAUGGCGAAACCCCGUCUCUACUAAAAAUAUAAAAAAUUAGCCAGGCAUAGUGGCGCAUGCCUGUUGUAGCCCCAGCUACUCAAGAGGCUGAGGCAGGAGAAUUGCUUGAACGCGGGAGGUGGAGGAUACAAUGAACCCGAGGUCGCGCCACUGCACUUCAGCCUGGGUGACAGAGCUAGACUCCAUCUCAAAAAAAAAAAAGAGCUAAAAAAUUACAUUUUACAAGUUUAUGGCCAGCCCACCUGUAAUAACAUUCUCUGAUAUUCCUUUACUUAGGAUGUCCCUAUUGAGAUCAUUUUUUAAAUUUAUGUGGAAGGAUUCUCUAGAUUAUUAUUAGAAUGAGCAAUUCAGUUUUGUUUGUUUUUGAGCCUGUCUUGUACCUGGUUGCACUAAAUAUAUAAUAGUUAUCUUUUGUGGAGACCUUAAAACCCUAAAUUUGAAUACAUGUUCAAUGAUAGUAAAGAUAUGACAGAAACUAGAAGAUAGCUGUUUAUGAUUUGAGCUUUUGGAAAAUUUUCGUUUCUUGAAUGUAAUAGUAUUUUUUCCUGAAUUGGAGGAGACUGAUCUAUAUUGUUUCAUUUUUCUUUUGUCCUAGUCUAUUUCACUUUCUUUUGUCAUAAUCUAUUUAAUUUCCCACUUUCUUAUUUUAGUAAAGAGAGAAUAAAUAGCAAGUGCAGGCCAGGCAUGGUGGUGCAGGCCAGACAUAGCGGUACAUGCCUGUAAUCCUAGCACUUUGGGAUGCCAAGGCGGGAGGAUUGCUUGAGCCCAGGAGUUCAUGCCUGAGCAACAUAGCAAGACCCUGGCUCUCUAUAAAACAGAAAACGCAAACUUUAAUAUUAUCAACAAUCAAUAUAUUAUAAGAGAUUGCAAUUUCUAAGUUUCUACCUGAGUGUUUCACAAAUACAAACUGGACAUUUUCCCUUUAAAUGAGUUUUAUUAUAAAAUGUACAUAUUGAUUGUAAAAACAAAAAAUUCAAAUAGUACAAAAGCAUAUAAGUAACUAAUAAAAGCUCCCUUUCUGCAUUAGGCCCCUCAGUUCUUCCCAGGGAAAAUGAUUAAUAGUUUACAUUCUUGCAGAAAUUUUUUAUGUAUAAAUUUUUACCCAAAUGAAUUCAUUAUAUAAAUUUUUUCCAACUUAGUGUUUUUUUACAUAAUAGUAGCAAGUUAAAAAAUUGUACUUCAGGCCAGGCACGGUGGGUCACGCCUGUUAAUCUCAGCACUUUGGGAGGCUGAGGCAGGAAGACCACUUGAGGUCAGGAGUUCAAGACCAGCCUGGCCAACAUGGUGAAAACCCAUCUCUACUAAAAUACAAAAAUCAGCUGGGCAUGGUGGCGCAUGUCUGUAAUCCCAGCUACUCGGGAGGCUGAGGCAGGAGAAUCGCUUGAACCCGGGAGGCGGAGGUUGCAGUGAGCUGAGAUUGCGCCAUUGCACUCCAGCCUGGAGGACAAGAGGGAGACUUCCUCUCAAAAAACAAAAUAUUGUACUUCAAAAAAUUAUUCUUCAAUGCUAUUUUUAAAUUACUAGAAAUUAUUUUGGAAUUUAAUGUUGCAUACAGCCUGAGAUAUGGCUGUUCACCCUUUGGUAAAGUAUUAAAGAAAAAUAAUGCAUUGUUCUCAGCUUAAAUUUUUUUCUGAUUUGACAACAUGAGUGAUGUUUUCCCAGUAUUAUUUCAAUUAUAUUUGUUUUAUUUUCUGUUCCUCACUCCUACCUCUCAUUCCAGUCCCCAAACUGGCUUUUCUUUUAUUUCUUUUUUCUUCAUUGCUGAUGUAUUUAUUGAGCAAUGUCCUGUAUCAGGCACUGUCCAAGGUGCUGUAUGUGCCAUGUUGAAGAGAACAGACAGGACCUACUGUCCUUGUAUAUCUUGCCUUUGAUAACAGAAACUGCAGGGGAUUGGAAUAGCCUCUUUACAAGAAAAGAAUAAGAGUGAGGAAAAGCGUUUGGAAUUUAUAGUGAUCACAGUGACCAGGUUUUGUAUUGGGUAUGUUUUACAUUUGUAACUUCAGUGCUAUUUUUUUUUAAGCUCCAUUGUUUUCUAAAUGUAAACAAGUAUCAAUGUAAGGACAGUUUCAUCAGGUGAAUAUCAGAAGUACUGACACCAUAAUCUCAUUUUGCACUGUGGCAAAGGGUAGUAGAUGUGUGUUCAGGAUUAUUUGCUCUGUCAGUAGUGCCCAGGGUGCCACUCCAUGACUAACCGAAACAUUUUAUUAUGUGACUCACUAAGAUGUUCAAUUCAUUAGUAUUUUCUGGUUACUCAAAGUGUACUCUAUGUACCUUUUUUUGACCUUUGAUUUUUAUUCUGAUGGAGAAGAUCAGAUUCCUUUUUUAUCUUAUAAAAAAUAAUUUUGAAACAAAGACUUAUUUUGAAGUAAGUCUUUUAACAUUAUCUCAGAUGCAUUUUAUUUUGUCCUUAAGUAAGACUUUUCAUUUUUACCUUUCAAAAUGCAAUUUUCAAAAUAUAUGCUUUUUUGAAACACUUAUUAUGUUACUGAAUAACCAGAGUAUUAAAUUCAAUGUACAGCAAAUUUUUACAAAGUCCCAGUAGUUCUUGCAGAGCUUUCUAUAAUAUCAGAUUUAUUUACCAUCAUGAAAUAUGUUUAUACAGUAUUAAGUAUAUUGUACUAUGAAGUUGGACCUGCACACUGAAAAAUUCCAAAAUACCUAUUAUGUUGUGCUUUUUGUGAUAUAUAUUCAUAUUAUUAUUUGUCAUAACAAGGUGAACUUUUUUAAAAUGGUAAACAUGUAUUAGUUACAUAAUCAGGAAAAAAGUCAUCUUUUAUAAUGAGAAAAAUUAGGUCAAGGAUAUUUCAGGUUUUAUCCAAUUAGAUUUCUUGUAAAGUUAUGUGUUUUCUUUUAUCUCAGUGCUUAUUUGCUUUGCAAGGAUGAAGGUUAGAGAUUCCUUUCAGUAGUUAAUGAAAGCUACAGACUUGUCUUGCCGAAAAAUGUACAUAAACACAUAAACUAUUUUCCAAGCAGUUUCACAGUGUUUGCAAAGUUCAGAUUGAAAACCCAGUUUUACAAAUCCCAUCUACAAAUUUGCAUUGUCAUUAAGAUAUAUUAAAAAUAAUUUUUCAAAGCAACAGCACAGAUGCACUUUAAAACUGUAGCUUAAAAAUAAAAAUUAGUAAUAUAACUUGUGUAAACCUACACAAAAGAUAAAAGAUAUCUUAUUGCAAAAAUAGGGCAACAUUUUGUUUUAAAGACCAAAUAGUGAAUUGAAUUUAAUGCAUAUCUUUAAAUCCUUAAUAGUAUCUCAAAUCUGGUUUAAAUCUGUCUCUCCUUAACGGAAUAGAAAGUGAAACAAAUCCAGAAAUCUUGUUCGAGUACAUGGUCUGUGCUAGUAAUCAUAUCUAAAGUGGUAAUGUUACCAUAUGCUGGGUACUGGGCUGAGUAAAUCACAUAUUUUAACUUAUUUAAACACUGCACUGUAUUGCCUGCUAGCGAUGUCAUUUUUUUAAAGUUGGAUGGUGAAUACAUGAGUUGUUUUUUAAACUCUUUUGGGAGCCUAAAAAAUUUGAAUUUUUUUUUUUCCCCCCCCAGACGGAGUCUCGCUCUCUUGCCAGGCUGGAGUGCAGUGACAUUAUCUUGGCUCACUGCAGCCUCUGAUUCCCUGGUUCAAGCAAUUCUCCUGCCUCAGCCUCCCGAGUAGCUGGGAUUACAGGCAUCCACCACCACGUCCAGCUAAUUUUUGUAUUUUUAGUAGAGACGGGGUUUCACCAUGUUGGCCAGGAUGGGAAAAUUUUUUAAAAGACAUUUAUUAAAAAAAAAUGUCUAUGCCUUAUCAAAGUUUAUAACUCAAGAAUUAAUGAGAUAAACAGUGGACAAAAAGUGUUGGCAGAUAACAUGCAUAAUUUUAAUUAAAAGUUAAGCAGUGAAAAAUAAACAUCUUUUUUUCUUAAAGAGAUAUUUCAUAUCUGUUCUAUUUGUUUAGUUUUAUUUAUUCUUUUUAGAGACAGGGUCUCUCUGUGGAGUGCAGUGGCAUGAUUAUAGCCCUCUGCGGCCUCAAUCUUCAGGGCUUAAGUUAUCCUCCUGCCUCAUCCUCCCAAGUAGCUAGGACUACAAGUGUGUGCCACCAUACCUGGCUAAUUUUUAAAAACUAUUUUGUAGAGACAGGGUCUUACUAUGUUGCCCAGAGUGGUCUUGAACUCCCAUCCUCAUGGAAUCCUCCCACUUCAGUCUCUGAAAGUGCUAGGAUUAUAGGCAUGAGCCAUUUAUGCCCAGCCAGUUUUCUUUUUUCUAAUUGAAGCUUGGCAAGCAGAGGGAAAUGUAUUAGGGAAAUAGCUUUAGUUUUGAGUGGGUGUCAGUAGCCAGCUGAAGAAAAAGCAAAAUGAAAUAGGUAGUAGAAAUGAGAAAGGGAGAGAGGGAAGAAGAAAAAAAUGGAUGUUGGAAAGUUGUUGCAUGUCUCUCUGGAUAGCUCAGAAGUAUCAGUUGUGGUUAUUGCCUCACUUGGCUUUUGUAAGCAUGAAAAAGCCAGGGACAAUUUCAACUACCAUUUCUGACCAUCAUCAACCACAAAUUUUAGGCAAUUUGUUAGAAUUUUUUUUAAAUGUUCUUAAUAGUUGUUGGGUACCUGGGAGAUUUCAGAGAAAGUAAUCACCUUUGUAUAUAUUAUUAAUGUGUUUAUAAUAGAAAUUAAAUUCUUUGGGAUGUACAGGUAAGAUAAGCUAUGUGAAGCAUAGCUGUUAUCCAAGUCGUGUGCCUUUGAAAUACUUGGAAUUUGAAGAACAGGACAUGCAGCUUAUGUUAUAAUUAAUUUGCGAGCAAUAUAUGGCAUGAUAGUAUUUUCUUAUCUAAAUUCUGAGUGCAUUGAAAGUUUAAAGCAAAGGACAAAAGCUUCCUUUGUUCAUGGCCCAUAUUCCAGUAUAUUUUUCUGAAACUGCCAAUAUUUUCUGAUCGGUACUUUCAUUUUUCUAGUUGGUUACCAAAUACUGUUAUUGGUAUUAUUUCUAUAUAAAAGGCUUUAAGAAGACUAUAGUAUAAUUUUCUUAAGAAAAAAGACAUGAUUAUAAGCUAAAAUAUGCCUUCGGUUUUGUGUGCUACAAAUUGAGGGAGAUUGAGAAUAUUUUAAAUCAAGGGCAGACAUUGAGUAAAAGCUUAUGACUUUGGAUGGAUUUGAAACAUGAUUAAAUGACAGAGUAAAUAAAAGCCCCUAGUCAAGUGAAUUCUAAUGGGGGAAAUAAGAGGACUAUAUAAAAAUUGAACCUCUGUUUUGAAAACAAAUCUUUCCAGGAAGUGGUACCACUCUGGGGUCAAGAGAAAUUGUAAGAACAAUAAAAUGAGCACACAUGACCUUCCUUUCCUAUAAAAAUAUGAAGCAGAAAACUCCCCCAUGAUUUCCUCAUGUUGCUUAGAAUAGUGUGUAUUUCAGAACUUUUCCAUUUAAUAUUUUUGGACCACAGUUGACUGAAACUGAGGAUGGGAGGAAGGGAUGCUUAAAACCUUGGAUAGUACCAAACCCUAUAUAUAUUAUGUUUUUUUCUAUAUAUACACAGCUAUGAUAAAGUUCAUAAAUUAGGCACAGUAAGAGAUUAAAAAUAUUAAAUUGGGCCAAUUAAUAUAUUGUAAUAAAAGCUAUGUUAAUGUGG